AAACACUCCAGCCGCUGAGAGCCCCCUUUGGCACUUGGCAGCACGCGGCGGCGGGCUCCUCGGCUCAACUUCGAGGAGUCUCCGCGACGCAACUUUUGGGGACGCUUUGCAUUUAAGAGAGAACGACCGAGGAGGAGGAGCGCUCUGCCCGGCCGCCGCUACCUGCGGGGAGCUCACCAGCAAACGCCACUGCAGACGAAGGACCCAAAGAACGUAAAGGGCAAACUGCCGCCGCGGGGAGGGGGCACCGCCGAGAAGUUAGAGUGUCCCAGAGACAACCUGCUCGAGCGCUCGGCCGGAGACACUAAGGCGGCCCGGGGCGCGGCGUGGCCCUGGGCUGGUCCCCCAGCCCCCUCCUCCGGGGCGGGAGCGACGCCGGGGCGCGACGAGCCCCGGCCGGCCGAGCGGGUCUCCGCGGGCAGCCAACAUUGAUUUCCUCCGGGCCGAGGGCGAGGGCCCGGGAGGCGGCGGGCUGCAGCCGCGGCAGGGCGAGAGCAUGUCCAAGCCGGUGGACCACGUCAAGCGGCCCAUGAACGCCUUCAUGGUGUGGUCGCGGGCUCAGCGGCGCAAGAUGGCCCAGGAGAACCCCAAGAUGCACAACUCGGAGAUCAGCAAGCGCUUGGGCGCCGAGUGGAAACUGCUCACAGAGUCGGAGAAGCGGCCGUUCAUCGACGAGGCCAAGCGUCUACGCGCCAUGCACAUGAAGGAGCACCCCGACUACAAGUACCGGCCGCGGCGCAAGCCCAAGACGCUGCUCAAGAAGGACAAGUUCGCCUUCCCGGUGCCCUACGGCCUGGGCGGCGUGGCGGACGCCGAGCACCCUGCGCUCAAGGCGGGCGCCGGGCUGCACGCGGGGGCGGGCGGCGGCCUGGUGCCUGAGUCGCUGCUCGCCAAUCCCGAGAAGGCGGCCGCGGCCGCCGCCGCUGCCGCCGCACGCGUCUUCUUCCCGCAGUCGGCCGCUGCCGCCGCCGCUGCCGCCGCCGCCGCCGCCGCGGGCAGCCCCUACUCGCUGCUCGACCUGGGCUCCAAAAUGGCAGAGAUCUCGUCGUCCUCGUCCGGCCUCCCGUACGCGUCGUCGCUGGGCUACCCGACCGCGGGCGCGGGCGCCUUCCACGGCGCGGCGGCGGCGGCUGCAGCGGCGGCCGCCGCCGCCGGGGGGCACACGCACUCGCACCCCAGCCCGGGCAACCCGGGCUACAUGAUCCCGUGCAACUGCAGCGCGUGGCCCAGCCCCGGGCUGCAGCCGCCGCUCGCCUACAUCCUGCUGCCGGGCAUGGGCAAGCCCCAGCUGGACCCCUACCCCGCGGCCUACGCUGCCGCGCUAUGACCCCGCGGGGCCGCCUCGCGAGGACCGGUGUGCACACGUGUACAUAUGUAUAGGUACGAGCGCUGCGGCCUCCCCGUGCGCCCUCCCGCGACCGGGGGCCCGGUUUGUAUGUACAUAGAAUGUAUAGGUGCCAGGUAGAGGCAGAGAGGCCAGGCGGGGCAGGAGUGGCCAAGCGCGCAAGGGCGCGGGCGAGCAGGCCUGUGAAUUCGCAGGAUCAUUUCAGACCCGCACUUCGGCAGCCAACUCGAAAGCAGGCGGUUGUGUGCGGCAGCAGUUGGCGUUUGCUUUGCACUUCGGAACCUGUUGCGUUUUGACCCACGGAGGUGGAGGAGUAACUUUUUGACAUGUUGGCCUUUCCAGUUUUGUUGGAAGUUUCAUGGUCGGUUUUGUUUUUGUUUCUCAUUCUUCUUCCUCGCCCCUCAGCCCCCCAACCCCCAACCCCCUCCCGGUCCGUGUUGCAUGCACGCUGUUCAAAUGUGAGGUCUGAAAUGGCUGGCACACGGGAAAAGCUGCUUGUGUCAUUCGUUUCUGGGAGUGGGAUGGCUCUGAGCAGCCUCGCCUCCCUGUUUGUACUAUUUGAACUUUGCAGAUCUCUGUUCUCUCAAGCAGAACUCCCAACCAGAUCCAUUCUUGACCAGUGACCGGCUCGAAUCUGGCCUUUUGUGUGAGAUGAUCACGGUUUCUUUUGUUUAUCACGCCAUUUGCAAAUCAGAGCAAGAGCUCUUUCUCAAGGGCAAGAAACGCAAACAAGAAAUAUUUGUGAGAUGAAAGUUGUCAAUUGGAUUUUCUUCCUAAACAAACAACAACAACAAACUACUAGAAGUCUCCCUGAGUCCACUCGCUUGGAUUUCUGACACAGUUUACAAAAAAGGAAAAAGGCACUGCUCCUAUUUUCCCUUAUGGCUGAGUUCACCUUAAGAUUGUAAAUGUGUAUAUGUCAGUGAAAACAUUGAGGCUUGGAAAAUGUGUUAUUUUCGUUGCCCUAAGUUUGAGUCGACUUUAGACUCAAAAACAUUUUGAGCGAAUAUCAAAGUUAACUUUUAAAAAUUGCGAAACUAUUUCAGAAUCGCAAUUUUAUCGAAGAUUAAAUCAGACUUUUUUGUCUGGUAAUUAUAUAUUUAUUAUUUAGCAAAACUGAAGAAAAAAAGCACAGAAUUGUUUCAACAGAUGUCUCUCAUUUUCAGCUAGCAUUUCUCUCCCAAGUUGAGCUGGUUUAAUGUGUUUUGGAUUUCCCUCCUCAAUUGGCUUAUUUUUUAGAUCACCUGCAAUUCAUUUGCAAAUUGCAAUAAAACACAUUUUAGAAAAAAGGAACCUUCAAUUAUUAGCUUUGUUUCUUUUUAAAUGUAUAUAUUUUGACUAAUGUUUGUGAAUGAAGUUGGCUAACAUGUAUUUAGUUUCAUUUUGGCUUUAUGUAAUAUAAAGUUUUUAAAAUUUUAAAUAUGGUUUUAACCUUUAUGUGUAAAUGAUUUUCUAGUGUGACCUUCUAAUUUAAUAUUAGACGUCUAAGGUAUAUCUGUAAAUUAGAAUCCGACUAUCACUCUGUUCAUUUUUUUUGAACAAAGAGUUUAAAUAAAGCCUGAACCAGGGAAAAGAAAAA